CCUUCCAUGCCCCCAGCGCCCCCAGACCCACCUCCCCGGGGAGGCGCGCGAGUCCCUCCGUCUCUCAGGCAGCUCCGAGGCCCGCAAAUGUCAACAAUCCGCCCUCACCCCCUCCACUCAGACCGCCCUUUGUCUACACACACAUCCAGGGACCAUGACGACCACCGGUCCUGCGUACAAGGCCAGUGCCUCCCCUCCCCAGCUGCGCAUCACCUCCCGCUUCCGGGCAUCUGCUCCCUUGGGUUGCAGAUGUUGCACUGUCAUCACCCAGCAGGCCUGGACCUUCCUGGGCGGGCUCAGCCGGGCCACACUCGCCAGGACCGGCGACAACUCCCAGCCCGGUCUAGGGCUUGCACUGAGCUCUCCAGGUCCCAGUGACAAGGCGAACUGGGGAGCCCCACCCGGCACCAUCGCCCCGGGAAAGGGACGGCAGAUGGCUGUCUGGAGGGGAGCCACCCAGGCCCACCUCGAGCUCAGGCCUUGGAUGGGGAGCUGGAGAGAGACUGCAGGGCGAGGGCUGUGCCUUGUGGGCUCAGCGCCUUCCUCCUCCUGGCCUGCAUUUUCCUCUUUCUCUUUCCUGCUCCGGCUAGAUACUGGAGCCCAUACAACCUGGUUCACCUGGGGUGCGGUGACACCCUUAGCCAGUGGCACCCUGGGGGCCCUCUGGGGGCCCACCCACUCCCUCUGCAGGUGCUCUCUGUGAACCCUCCCACUCCCUCUGUGAGCCCACCCACUCCCUCUGUGAACCCACCCUCUCCCUCUGUGGGUGCCCUCUGUGAGCCCAUCUACCACCUCUGUGAAUCCACCCACCCCCUCUGUGAACCCACCCACCCCCUCUGUGAGCCCACCCACCCCCUCUGUGAGCCCACCCACUCCCUCUGUGAACCCACCCACUCCCUCUGUGGGUGCCCUCUGUGGGCCCUCCCACUCCCCUGGCUGAGGCCUGCUGUGCCCAGGAGCAGCCCGAGAUCCUGUAGAGGUUCCGGGAGAGCACUCAUGAAACCCAGGCUCCUCCCAAACUCUGCCCUCACCCCCAUCCUUUGUUGUAGGUUUUCACUUCCUGCACGCAGGUGGGAGAUGAGAAGGGCUCAGAGGGGUGUGGGCGGCAGGAGUGGGGAAGCCCUCCUGUUGCCCCCGCUGUGAGCCCACCGCUUGGUUUUGGCUGAGAGAGGGGCCAGAGAGGGGAAGAAGAGGGGCUUCAGGGAGAAGGGAGGGAGCCAGGGCUAUGCUGAGUGGGGCUGCAAACUCUGGAGGAGGAAUGAGAAUCCCAGCGCCUGUGGGUAGGAGCGCCCUGGGGCUGCUGCAGCACAGUUGCACCAACUGGACUGAAACCCACUUGUCCCACCACCCUCUGCCGCUGUCCUCACAGGGCGCCUUUGCUCUGCUCUGUCCUCCCUCUUUUUACAGGGACACCAGUCACUGGAUUCAGGGCCCACUCUAAACUCAGGGAGAUAUCCUGAGAUCCAGAGCUUAAUUACACCUGCAAAGAUGCUAUUUCCAAACAAAGUCACAGUCACGGGUACCAGGGGUGGGACUUGGGCAUAUCUUUCGGGGGACACCAUUCAACCCACGACACUAAGGUUCUGGAUGGGGGUCAGUAGAAAGCUGGCUGUCAGCCUGGGAGGACCCAGGUACUGUGGGGCCAUGGGCCCAAAUUGUGUGGCUGGAGCCCUGCUCAAGGUGGGGUCAGGCCGGGCGCAGGGUGGUGUCCUGCCCAUUUGCAGCCGUCCUCCUUCCCUCAGCCCACUCCAGGGCUGGUGUCCCAAGAAGAGGCUUGAGACGUCAUCUGCACCCAUGUUGCCAAACCCAAGAGUUGCCCAGUCCAUGCUGUGCAUGCAGGGCAGGCAGGUGGAAGCCUCCCUGAAUGAGACAGGUGUGAAGAGGGAGUGGGACAGCCAGCGAGUAGGGUCAGCCUCCCAACGCUUGAGGUCCCUUUAGUCUGGGAAGCUGAGGGUGGAGGGUGCAGGCCAGGUGGGGCCACAGUUGGUUCAUCGCUCACGCACUUCUUCACCUCCUGGGUGUCCCUCAGGGUGCCUGUGGUCCAGCUGGGGCUGACAGAGGGUGGCUCUCUAGAUAGGACCCAGCUAUGUGGUCAGAGUGAUGGGAGAUUUUAUAGGGGGUUCCACCAGAAGCUGGGGGACAGGGAGAGGGGAGAAAAGAGCCCCAGAGCUUGCAAGACAGGAGUCCAGGUCGCACAGGGUAUGGUCUAUUUCGCACACACUGGGCGGCAGGCCCAGGGAUGCCGUAACAGCAGCUCUGCCUCUUGCCAUCUCACGGAAGGUGACUGUCUGUCAGCCGUGGCAAACUGCCAGCACCAUCUCCUUCCAAAGGCAGAAAACAGAUUCCUGGGGAGUCUGCAGGCCUUCCCAGCACUCUUUGUGGUGUUCCAUCCUCCCAAGGGGUGGAGCCGGCUGGGAUGCAGGCCAGCUGUGUGGCCUCUGCUGCAGCCCUGCUGACCGGCCCAUAUGGGAUUUAGGAAGCCUUAGACGGCCUGGUAUGCUCAGGCCUGUGGGGGUUAGGGUGAGGGUUAGGGUUGUCGAGGGGGGCUACAUUGUGGAGGCUCACCAUGGCCUUGACCCCACUGGAGGUCAGGUCCGGGCAGCUCCUGCUGUCAGGAAGGGGCCUGUGGCGGAGCAUUUCAGGUUCAGCUCCUUUGCUUCAGUUCAGGGGUUCACCAAUCCUCCCACCACUGACCUCCGCCCAGCCUGCUCUUUUCCAGGGACAUCUGGUGCCUGUGUCCUUCUUGACCAUCAGGAAUUAGUGGCUCAGUUCACGUGGUCAUGUGGCCACCUGUCCCCCACCUCAUGCACUGCACAGUCCAUUGGCAGACGGCUUGUGGGGUGACAUCUGUCAAACGUGUCAGCACUCCAUUGAGUUCUGGUUGUAGGCGAAGGUUAACGCUCUCAAGAGCCAUCUCAGGCCAUGGGUCCCCCCCCAGGGGACCCCACCCUAGGGGACCCACAGCUGGGUGAAGCCAAGGCAGACAUGCACCUUAUUCAUCUCUGUGUCCUUAGGGCUGAGCACAGGGGAUGGUGCGUAGGAGUCCCCAGAUAAUGUUUGUUGAAUGACUGACAGAAAGAUGCCUGGGUCCUGAGGCCUGCUGCCUUGUGGUCACUCACCUGGCCCCGAUACCUGUGCAGACUCAGUUAUCUGGCCAACAGGUCCACCCUUCAGACUUGCCAUGUCAGGAAGUUCUGGACCCCUGGGAAGAUGGGGUCUGCAGGGUCCAGCGACAGAGCAGCCAAUUCCAACUCAAUUGUUGGUCCAGCUGCAUAGACUAGGUGAGCAAGUGCCAGGUAGGUAAAGGGGACUCAGGACCAGCCACGGAGCUGAGACGGGCCUUUACAGGGAGCUCAUGUGGUGGACAAGGGCUCUCAGGGCCAUCGACGGCCACUGGACGUCCAGCCCAGGGAGGAGCCCACUGACCCCAUCAGACUCUGGCUGCUAGAGGUCUGGGCCUGUUUAGGACAGCACAUGCUCUAACCCUCUAAAGGGGACUCCACCUCCAGGGGCCACCCGGCUGCCCUCCUGCCAGUGUGAGGGCAAGGCCUGUGUGAGGUCUGUUUGAGGGGCACAUGGCACGUCCAGAGCUUGUGGAGCAGAGGCCAUGUCUCAGGUGCCAGCUUCCUCUUCCUAUGGGGGUGUCUUUCAUGCAGAGUCUGGGCCCUGAGAGCUCGUGCCCAGAAGUGUGAAAAUUAGUCUGGGGGUAGCUUUUUGCAGAGGAGUGUCAUCUUGAUGCUCCAUUAUUGGCUGCUGAGUGAAUGAGUGAAUGAAUGAAUGAAUGAAUGAAUGAGUAAAUGAAUGAAUGAAUGAAUGAAUGAAUGGAUGAAUGAAUGGAAUGGCACCUGUGCUUCAGAGAGGCUUGCCAUUUCGGGGCAGAAGGGUUUGCUGAGGCAGCCGUGGGCCUGGGGCAGCUGUGCUGAGGGAGGAUUGAGCACGUGGGCUGGCAGCAGUUUGUGGUUGGCGGGCCGGAGGGAUGCUGCGUUAAACUCAUCUGCCUGCCCGUGCCGGCGCUGAGCCUUCACAUUGCUGGGCUUUCCAGGACAGCGGUCACCAUGGAGAUGGCACAUCCUGGCAGGGCACCCUGAGCGGCAGUGAAGAGAGACAGGGUUAACCCUGCAUGUGCCGGGCUCCUGUUCCUGACCACUGUCCUGGCCUGGCCUUGGUGAGGGAGGGGCUGGGUGGCCCUGUGACCUCUGGGGAGCUGGAUCCGGGGAUGCUCUGGACACAUCCAAUUCUUCAACGACCUGGACAGCCUGGGCAGGAUCCCUGGAAACCGACCAGAAAGGAAUGAGAGGAACAGACCGAGGCUGUCAGCUGGCAGCGGCCCCAGCCUGGGGUCCCUUCCCUAUCUCAUGGGGAACUCCUCGAUCUGGUCAUGGGAGAAGACUCCAAAAUCGGGCCAUUUCAUAGGGAGAGCUUUGGAUGUGGCGCUGUGAUGGGGGUUGUGGCUUGUCUACUGGCACACGGUACCCACUCUCCAGCCAUCUUCAGCCAUGAGGCCUGGGCAGAGGCUCGGUCACCCCCCACGCGUACGUGUGUGAGUCCUGCUGGUCCUGCCCUCGUUGGUGUGGUUGUUGGAUCACAGCCCAUGGCUUUAAGAGUGUCCCUGUGUCCUCUCCCCUUGUCUGGGACUCCCUGGGGUGGCUCAAACCCUCCCGUUCCUGGGGGGUGGUUCUGCUGUCAGCCCAGCAGUCACCAAAACAGUGUGUCCGGGACUGGGGCCAGUGGACGGGCUCCUUGGAGGCACCAGAUGUUACAAAGCAGCCUGGUGUCGCCUGCUCUGAGUUGGGCGCUGUGGCCUGGGUUUAUCCUCAGCACGUUGGCUGGGGCACCUCCCGGGGCCAGGACUUCGUCUUUUGUAUCACUCUGCCCUCUGUGUCCAGCACAGGGCGAGCAGGUGCUCAGAAAGUGCCUGCUGAAUGAAUGAACAGACAAUGCGCUGGCCUCCACUUUGCCUCAUCAGCAGCUGCCGAGUUCGGAUGACGGUAGCGUUGAUGUUUUCUUGGCUGAGAUUCCAGGGAGACCUUGUUUAUUAAAUGAUCGCUGUGAAGCUGUUUCUGUGGGUCACCUCCCUUAGAUCCAGUGUGCUGACAGCAUGCAGGCUAACAUCGAGCCUGCUGGCAGGUGAGAGGCGGGAGCAGCCCCUUCUCAGCCAUGCUGCUAGUGCUGGUGUCCGCCCGUGAGGAAGUCCCCCUCAGGGCUCCCACUGGAGGGACAGUCCCUAUCCCUACCCCCUCUCCCUACCCCCCGGAGCCUCCGUGUGCAUUCCAGGCUGAGCCCACCCCAGGCCCAUUCGAGGGACUUUGAAUCUUGAUGGAGCAAUUCAGAGAUGAUGGACGUUUGCAGGCCAGGCAGGAGGGCCGGGUGGGGUGGGUGUCCCGACCACCUGCCCGGUAUCCUCAGAAGAGGAAACACGAGCAUCCUCUGAAAGCCAUGGCCGUGUGCGCCCUGGCAGAGGCCUCAGACCCCUGGGGCAGUGUGGCCCAGCCCUAAGUGAGCUCCUUCCUCAUGGCCCUGCCUCCUGCGCUCCCCAUGCUCUGGCCCUGGUCAGAUGGGCCCAAUCACAGCCUGGCCUUUUAAGUUUAAAUGGAUAAAUCAGAGCUGGCCCAUCAAGCAAGUCCUACCAGGGGUCCAGGCCACGCGCUGAUGACCUGCGGGUGAAUGGAAGCUCUCGGCAUCACAGGCUGGGGUCUUGUAAACAACAGGCAUUUACUGCUCACACUUCCGGAGGCUAGAGGUCUGCGAUCCAGGCUGGGAUCCAGGCCCCACUUUCUAACCCCUCAGUGGACUGGAACAUAUGGAUUUGGGGGGACACAAGCACCUGGGCCAGAGUUGCUGGUGACUGUGGCUGGACGGCUUUGGAAGGGUGUCAUUCACUUCCACCCUGGGUGCAGCCUCUUUUAUGAAAUGCUCCUUCUUCUCCGCCUUCCUGAACCUCCUGGUCAGCGCCUUCGUGGUCUUCCUGGUCUUCAUUGCCAGCACCAUCGUGAGCGUGGGCUUCACCAUGUGGUGCGACACCAUCACCGAGAAGGGCACCGUACCCCACAGCUGUGAAGAGCUCCAGGACAUCGACUUGGAGCUGGGCGUGGACAACUCCGCCUUCUACGAUCAGUUUGCAAUUGCCCAGUUUGGCCUCUGGGCCUCAUGGCUGGCCUGGCUGGCCAUCACCACGCUGGCCUUCCUGAAGGUCUACCACAACUACCGUCAGGAGGACCUGCUGGACAGCCUGAUCCACGAGAAGGAGCUGCUGCUGGCCCGGCCGUCCCCACGCACCUCCUUCCAAGAGGAGAAGAGCGCUGUCAUUUAGGCACAGUGCAGGCAGGGGGAGCUGGCCCCGACCUCCCUGCUGCGCUCGGGGGCACGGGCCUGCCUGGGGAAGCAGCUGGGGGGCUCUGCCUGGGCCCUGGCCACAUGCAGCCCUGCGUGUGUCCCCUCGACGCCACGUGUAGUGAGGUGAGCGCCCCAGUGCCCACCUGUGAGCCUGGCAGUGGACUGGGUGGGUGCCGGCUCCCUGAUGAGGAUGGUGCAGAGAGACUAUGGGUGUGGGGCGGGGGCGGGGGGCACCUCCAGGCCUCGCACAGGGCCCCUUGGCUGUCCCAGUAGGACCUGACUGGCCAGCCUAUGUGGAGGGCGUCCAGCUUGUCUCCCCCAACCCUGGCCGGAUGCUGUCUCCAUGCCAGCUGGCCCAGGGGUGGCCAGAUGUCACUUAGCCCUGAACGAAUUCUGCAUGAAUUCUGCCAUCCAGGCAGAGGCUGCGUGUGGGGAGGAGCUCACGGCACCUUCCAGCCUCUGGCCCCAGGUUGGCCCCCUCCCCAGCUGAGUCCCCCUCCUGGGUGGGUGCCAUAGGCCUGGGAGACCCUGUGGCCGGGCUCAGGGAGGCUUCUGAGGCCUGUGAGUUCACCUCACUGUGUGUGGGUCCUGUCUGUGCUUGGCUGAGGGUCAGGGAAGUGGUAAUCUGGGCUCCACAGAAUCGGGGGCAUCAUCUGGUUGGGGAUUUCGGGGGCACACGUACCACAUAGAGGACUGGGCCAGGAGCCAUGGCAGGGGUCUGUGUGUGGGUGAGUAUGGGAGGAUGUGAUUGUGAGUGCCUUUGUGCAUGGGAGGGUGUGAUUGUGUAUAUGAGUGCAUGAGAGGAUGUGACUGAGUGUGCAUGUGUGGGUGUGACAGUGCAGGUGUGACUGCAUGUGAAGGUGUCACUGAGUGUGCACGAGAGGGUGUGACUGCAUGUGAGAGUGUGUGACUGCAUGGGAGGAUAUGAGUGUGCAUGAGUGUGCAUGUGAGGGUGUGACUGAGUGCAUGAGAGUGUGACUGCCUGUGAGUGAAUGUGUGACUGCAUGUGCGAGUGACUGCCUGGGAGGAUGUGAUUGUGCAUGAGUGUGCAUGUGGGUGUGACUGCAUGUGAGGGUGUGACUGUUGUGCGUGUGAAGGCUUGAUUGUGAGUGUGCCUGGGAGGAUGUGAGUGUGAGGGUGUGACUCCCUGUGACAUGAGUGUGCAUGCAUGUGAGUGUGAGGAAGAGUGUGUAGGUGUGAGUGUCUAGGCAGGUGUGUCUGCAGUGUGUGCAGCAUGUGCGUAAGUGCAUGUGAAUGUGCGUGUGUUGCAUGUGAGCAUGUGCACGCCUGUGCGUGUGAGCAUUGUGUGCGUGAUGGGAGCCGUGGGUGCUGUGUGGACAGCCCCUCUGCCCCUCCCAUGGGCUCCCACGCCCAGCAUCCACCUGAGAGAGGAGGGAGCUGCCUUCCCAUUCUGCAGAGUCUGUGUGCUGAGGCCCCGCAGAAGCAAGUGGAGGAGCUGGGAUGUGAACCUGGGACCCCGGCGUAGGGGGCUGCUUGGCUGUGGACCCUGCCCCUCAGGAAAGCCCAGGGUCCACCUCCAGAGGACUCGUUCUGGGGCGGGGGCGGAGGCGGGGGGCCUCCCCACCCGGGGCUCGAUGAGGGGCUGUCCGUUUCUUGGCUCGAGUGCUGCCAAGUGCUCCCUGCUGCUGCGCCCACCUUCCCGGGGAGAGGCGAGCCCCUGGCUCCCUGAGUUCAUGACCCACCCUGUCCACCAUCAGCAGCUGGCUUGUGUCUCUGGGUGGCUGGGCACCAGCCUCCUGGAGGCCACGUGCCUGGGUCCACAUGGAGGGUCCUGGUGGGGGCAUCAUCCUGGGUCCCGGGAGUGAGGCUGGCAGGUGCCCAUCGGGGGUGUCAAGUCCAGGGGGAUCGAGGCUCUGGAAGCUCAAGGGGGCUCUGGCCUUGGGGACCAGCUGAGUUUCCAGCUGGCAGCCAGGUCCUCGAGGGAAGGGGUUUGGACAGAAUCCGAGGCCCCCUAAGCUGAUGGGGUCCCCUGUCUCCCCUUCCAGCCCUGACCCACUGGACAUGGGGACUCUUUCCAGUCCGGAGAGCUCCUUGUCUGUGUCCCCAGCAGAAGGUGGGGUGGCUCCUGCCUCACCCUCUGCCCAGCCCUGAUCCAGGCCACAGCCAUCUAGGGCCCUGAAGGAGGGGCAGGAGGCAGGGGUGGCUUCUGGAACCUGAGGCUUGGCCCCGGUUGGGUCUGUUCUUGGGGGCUGCACUGCUGGAUCCCAGGAGCAGGUGUGGAACAGCCCCAUGGCCAGGGUGAUGGAAAUCCUCGGCUGCAUGCAGACAUAGACCCACCCUGGACUGGGCUGUCUCCGGAGCCCAGACACAUCGCCCUGGGAAGGGGCAGCUGGGCCUGCAGUGUGCUGGGCAGGGGCUGGCGGCCCUGGUCGUGGGCUCUCCAGGGUCCCUCAGGGGAUUGGGCCUCUCCCCAGGCAGGAAGGUGGGAAGUGCAGGCAUGACCCGGGGUUCCUGAGGCUGGUCCACCAAGUUGCUUCUGAGACGCCUUCGCUUCUGUCCUGGCUGGCUGUUAAUGAUAUCCCUGUUCUAAUUCCACUCUGGCUAAACUGAAAGUAAAGAUCCUUAAGCUUA